AGACAGUCUCUGUCAUGCAGGCUGGAGUGCAGUGGCACUAUCUCGGCUCACUGCAAAUUCUGCCUUGCUGGUUCAAGCAGUUCUCAAGCCUUAGCCUCUUGAGUAGCUGGGAUUAUAGGCAGGUGCCACCAUGCCCAGCUAAUUUUUUGUAUUUUAGUAGAGAUGGGGUUUCACCAUGUUGCCCAGGCUGGUCUUGAACUCCUGAGCUCAGGCAGUCUGCCUGCCUUGGCCUCCCAAAGUGCUAGAAUUACAGGUGUGAGCCACCACAUUCAGCCAAAACCUCUUUUUGACAAAGUUCAGCCUCAUCCUAUAGGUGAUUUUGUACUCUCUGCUAAGAUAAAAUUUUCUCCAAAUUGUUAGCCUUAGGAUAAAGGACAAUUUAUGAACCAAAAAAAACUCUUUGUUUCCUGAACAGUCAAUUUAGUUAUUGUACUAAGAAGUCUGUCAGACAAGACUUGUUGUAUUGCAGUCACCUCAGCUUUCAAGAAGGAUGUUUAUCUGUGUAUCAUUGCUGUUGUCUUGAGUUGUGUUUUUUGAUUCUGCUGGUCUUGUUACUAUAACUUAGCGUUAGUUUAGUGACAUUGCUAAGAUAAUGACAUUGAUUAUCUGUGAGGAGUCACAGAUAGGUGAACAUUUUUGUUUGCCUAAUAUCUUUGAAUGAUAGAAAAUUUUAGUUUUGGUUAUAAUUUUGAAUGAGUUGGAAAACAGACAAAACACUGUUCUAUUUUUUUUUUGAGACUGGGUCUGGCUCUGUCACUCAGGUUGGAGUAGCUCUGUUGCCCAGGCCAGAGUGCAGUGUGCGACCUCACCUUACUGCAACCUCUGCUUCCCAGGCUCAAGGAGUCUUCCCACCUCAGCCUCCCCAGUAGCUGGGACUACAGGCACAUACCACCAUGGCCAGCUAAUUUUUUAAUUUUUUGUAGAGGCGGGGUUUCACCAUGUUGCCCAGACUGCUCUUAAACUCCUGAGCUCAAGCAGUCUGUCUGCCUCAGCCUCCCAAAGUGCUGGGAUUACCAGUGUGAACCUCUGUGCCCAGCCCAAACUCGGUUCUUAAGGUGCUUAUACUUAAAAAAAAAGAAAGAAAAAAGGCAUCUGUACAUCUUCUUUACCCAAAUGAUGUUUAGUUUACACUAGAGUUUUUGAUGUACGUAUCUUGGUACCUCAGAAUAGCAACUAGAAUGUUUUGCCUUCAUUAUAAAUAAAAUUAUUUAGAAAUAGCAGUGGUGUUAAACAAUAUAUUUUUAGUAUCCCUUGAGUGAUCCCAAGUAGUUAUGCCAUUUAAAAAAAAAGACACCAAGAGAAUACUGGGUUAUUUUGUUUUAGAAGAAGAUAUAUUUUACUGCUGUAAAUUAGAGUGGAAAACUGUCUUAUAGCAUACAUUUAGAGAAUGUUAAUCCUGGAAGUCAGUUGCUGUUCGAUACAUAGACUGUUUGGUCUGUAAGGAGCAAGAACAUACUAAUUUUAAGGGAAGAAACAUCUUCGAAGGCAGAAUAGAAUCUAUAAACUGCAUCAUUUAGCCAUUGGAUAACAAAGUCUACAGUAGAGCUUGCAGCUGGUUGGCUUAAACAGGAAAGUAGCCCUGAACAAGUAUUAAUAUACUCUGUGCAGCCCUUAGGGCAUGGAAAUUGAAGUGCAAGCAGUGUAAUAGCCACCAAGAUUGUUACACGGAGAAUGGAGGAAUGUGAAGGACUCUUCUUAGCCGUAUGAAGAUAACACCAAGUAUUCUCAUUCAGCAAGUGGCCGUACCGCUAUGCAUCAUUGCCCGUCCCCUCUCUCCCUCCAGCCACAUAUGAGAGUUCCAGUUUCUCACCAACAUUUAGUCUUCUUAGUCUUUAAUUUUAACCAUUCUGAUCCAGGAUGAGAAGACUGAUAAAAGAAGAAGCUAGCUGAACAGCUGUAAAAUGCCCAAAUCUGGGUUCACAAAACCAAUUCAGAGUGAAAAUUCUGACAGUGACAGCAAUAUGGUAGAGAAACCAUAUGGAAGAAAGAGUAAAGACAAGAUUGCAUCCUACAGCAAAACUCCAAAAAUUGAACGAAGUGAUGUGAGCAAGGAGAUGAAAGAGAAAUCAUCCAUGAAACGUAAACUUCCUUUUACUAUUAGCCCAUCAAGAAAUGAAGAACGAGAUUCAGACACAGAUUCAGAUCCAGGACAUACAAGUGAAAAUUGGGGGGAGAGACUUAUAUCUUCUUACAGGACAUACUCAGAGAAAGAAGGUCCAGAAAAGAAGAAGACAAAAAAGGAAGCUGGAAAUAAGAAAUCCACACCAGUUAGCAUUCUUUUUGGUUAUCCACUCUCUGAGCGAAAACAGAUGGCACUUCUUAUGCAGAUGACAGCAAGAGACAACAGUCCAGAUUCCACACCAAAUCAUCCAUCACAAACAACGCCUGCCCAAAAGAAAACUCCCAGUUCUUCAUCUCGACAGAAAGAUAAAGUUAAUAAAAGAAAUGAACGUGGUGAAACUCCUUUACACAUGGCUGCUAUUCGAGGAGAUGUGAAACAAGUUAAAGAAUUAAUAAGUUUAGGGGCAAAUGUGAAUGUGAAAGAUUUUGCAGGUUGGACACCACUGCAUGAAGCUUGCAAUGUUGGAUAUUACGAUGUUGCUAAGAUACUUAUAGCAGCUGGAGCAGAUGUUAACACACAAGGAUUAGAUGAUGACACUCCACUCCAUGAUUCUGCUAGUAGUGGGCACAGAGAUAUAGUAAAGCUGUUACUUCGUCACGGUGGAAAUCCAUUUCAAGCUAAUAAACAUGGGGAGCGUCCAGUGGAUGUAGCAGAAACAGAGGAGUUGGAGUUGCUACUAAAAAGAGAGGUGCCUUUAUCUGAUGAUGAUGAAAGUUACACAGAUUCCGAAGAGGCUCAAUCUGUAAAUCCUUCUAGUGUUGAUGAAAAUAUUGACUCUGAAACAGAGAAAGACUCUCUCAUCUGUGAAAGUAAACAGAUACUUCCCAGUAAAACACCUCUUCCAUCUGCCCUUGAUGAGUAUGAGUUCAAAGAUGAUGAUGAUGAAGAAAUUAAUAAGAUGAUUGAUGAUAGGCAUAUUCUUAGGAAAGAACAACGAAAAGAAAAUGAACCUGAAGCAGAAAAAACUCAUUUAUUUGCAAAACAGGAGAAAGCCUUCUAUCCUAAAUCAUUUAAAAGUAAAAAACAAAAGCCAUCUAGGGUCUUAUAUUCAAGUACUGAAAGUUCUGAUGAAGAAGCUCUUCAGAAUAAAAAGAUUUCUACUUCAUGUUCCGUCAUCCCUGAAACAUCAAAUUCUGAUAUGCAAACCAAAAAGGAAUAUGUAGUUUCAGGUGAACACAAACAGAAAGGCAAAGUUAAAAGAAAAUUGAAAAAUCAGAAUAAAAAUAAAGAGAACCAAGAGCUAAAGCAAGAAAAGGAAGGAAAAGAAAAUACAAGAAUAACAAACUUGACAGUAAAUACUGGACUAGAUUGUUCAGAAAAGACCAGAGAGGAGGGGAACUUUAGGAAAUCUUUUAGCCCAAAAGAUGAUACUUCAUUACAUUUAUUUCAUAUUUCCACUGGUAAAUCUCCCAAACAUUCUUGUGGAUUAAGUGAAAAACAGUCAACACCACUAAAACAAGAACAUACUAAAACAUGUUUAUCACCAGGAAGUUCUGAAAUGUCAUUACAGCCUGAUCUUGUUCGGUAUGAUAAUACAGAAUCUGAAUUCUUGCCAGAAAGUUCAAGUGUAAAAUCUUGUAAGCAUAAGGAAAAAAGCAAACAUCAGAAAGAUUUCCACUUAGAAUUUGGUGAAAAAUCAAAUGCCAAAAUAAAGGAUGAAGAUCAUAGUCCAACAUUUGAAAAUUCAGAUUGCACACUGAAAAAAAUGGAUAAAGAAGGUAAAACAUUAAAAAAACAUAAAUUGAAGCAUAAAGAGAGGGAAAAAGAAAAGCAUAAAAAAGAAAUUGAAGGUGAAAAGGAAAAAUACAAAACUAAGGAUAGUGCCAAAGAACUGCAGAGGAGUGUGGAAUUUGAUAGAGAAUUUUGGAAAGAGAAUUUUUUUAAAAGUGAUGAAACUGAAGAUCUCUUUUUAAAUAUGGAACAUGAAUCCUUAACAUUAGAAAAAAAAUCAAAAUUGGAAAAAAACAUCAAAGAUGAUAAAUCAACCAAGGAAAAGCAUGUGUCAAAAGAGAGGAACUUUAAAGAGGAACGAGACAAGAUUAAAAAGGAAAGCGAGAAAUCUUUUAGGGAGGAAAAAAUAAAAGAUCUAAAAGAAGAGAGAGAAAACAUACCCACAGAUAAAGACUCAGAAUUUACUUCUUUGGGUAUGAGUGCCAUUGAGGAAUCUAUAGGGCUUCAUUUAGUGGAAAAGGAAAUAGACAUUGAAAAACAAGAAAAGCAUAUAAAGGAAAGUAAAGAAAAACCUGAGAAGCGAUCUCAAAUUAAAGAAAAGGACAUUGAGAAGAUGGAAAGAAAAACCUUUGAAAAAGAAAAGAAGAUAAAACAUGAGCAUAAGUCAGAAAAAGACAAAUUAGAUCUUAGUGAAUGUGUUGAUAAAAUAAAAGAAAAGGACAAGCUAUAUUCGCAUCACACAGAAAAAUGCCAUAAAGAAGGUGAGAAGAGCAAAAAUACUGCUGCUAUUAAAAAAACUGACGACAGAGAGAAAAGUAGAGAAAAGAUGGAUAGGAAACAUGACAAAGAAAAGCCUGAAAAAGAGAGGCAUCUAGCAGAAAGCAAAGAAAAGCACUUGAUGGAGAAAAAAAAUAAACAAUCAGAUAAUAGUGAAUACAGUAAAUCAGAAAAAGGCAAAAAUAAAGAAAAAGACAGGGAGCUAGAUAAAAAGGAAAAAUCUAGAGAUAAAGAAAGUAUAAAUAUAACUAACUCCAAACACAUACAGGAAGAAAAAAAAUCAAGUAUAGUAGACGGUAAUAAAGCACAACAUGAAAAACCCUUAUCCCUUAAAGAAAAAACAAAAGAUGAACCUUUGAAAACUCCAGAUGGAAAAGAAAAAGAUAAAAAAGAUAAAGAUAUAGAUAGAUACAAAGAACGAGACAAACAUAAAGAUAAAAUUCAAAUAAAUAGCUUACUCAAACUAAAAUCUGAAGCAGAUAAGCCUAAACCUAAGUCAUCACCAGCAUCAAAAGAUACCCGACCUAAAGAAAAGAGGUUAGUGAAUGAUGAUUUAAUGCAGACAAGUUUUGAACGAAUGCUAAGCCUUAAAGACCUAGAAAUAGAACAGUGGCACAAAAAACAUAAGGAAAAAAUUAAGCAAAAAGAAAAGGAACGGUUGAGAAACCGAAACUGUUUAGAACUUAAAAUAAAAGAUAAAGAAAAAACAAAGCAUACACCAACUGAAUCCAAAAAUAAAGAACUUACUAGGUCAAAGAGUUCAGAAGUGACUGAUGCAUAUACCAAGGAGAAACAACCUAAAGAUGCUGUAAGUAACAGAUCACAAUCUGUUGACACCAAAAAUGUAAUGACUUUAGGGAAGUCAUCUUUUGUUUCAGAUAAUAGCUUAAACAGGUCUCCUAGAUCAGAAAAUGAAAAGCCGGGUCUCAGCUCCAGAUCUGUAUCCAUGAUUUCUGUUGCUAGUUCAGAAGAUUCCUGCCAUACUACAGUGACAACCCCAAGGCCUCCAGUUGAGUAUGACUCUGACUUUAUGUUAGAGAGUUCAGAAUCCCAAAUGUCCUUUUCCCAGUCACCUUUUUUGUCAAUUGCCAAAUCUCCUGCUCUUCAUGAAAGGGAAUUGGACAGCCUGGCUGACUUGCCGGAGCGGAUUAAACCACCAUAUGCAAACAGACUUUCAACAUCCCAUCUUAGGUCAUCUUCUGUAGAAGAUGUUAAACUAAUUAUAAGCGAGGGGAGACCUACCAUAGAAGUUCGAAGAUGUAGCAUGCCUUCUGUCAUUUGUGAACAUACCAAACAAUUCCAAACAAUAUCAGAAGAGAGCAAUCAAGGUAGCUUAUUAACUGUGCCAGGAGAUACUAGUCCUUCUCCCAAACCUGAGGUAUUCUCAAAUGUGCCUGAAAGAGACCUUUCAAAUGUAUCUAACAUACAUUCCAGUUUUGCAACUUCUCCAACUGGAGCUUCAAACAGCAAGUAUGUUUCAGCUGAUAGAAAUCUCAUCAAGAAUACUGCCCCAGUGAACACUGUAAUGGACAGUCCAGUGCAUUUAGAGCCAUCUAGUCAGGUUGGUGUGAUCCAGAAUAAAUCAUGGGAGAUGCCUGUUGAUAGACUAGAGACAUUAAGCACCAGAGACUUUAUCUGCCCAAAUUCUAACAUACCUGAUCAAGAAUCCUCUCUUCAGAGUUUUUGUAAUUCUGAAAAUAAGGUAUUGAAAGAAAAUGCUGAUUUUUUAUCCCUGCGCCAGACUGAACUGCCAGGAAACUCUUGUGCUCAGGAUCCGGCAUCCUUUAUGCCUCCACAGCAGCCUUGCUCUUUCCCCAGCCAAUCACUUUCAGAUGCUGAAUCGAUUUCUAAACAUAUGUCUUUGUCAUAUGUUGCUAAUCAAGAGCCAGGUAUUUUACAACAAAAAAAUGCAGUUCAGAUUAUUAGUUCUGCUUUAGAUACUGAUAAUGAAUCUACAAAAGAUACAGAAAAUACUUUUGUCCUAGGAGAUGUUCAAAAAACAGAUGCCUUUGUCCCAGUGUACUCUGACAGCACUAUUCAAGAAGCAUCACCAAACUUUGAGAAAGCUUAUACUUUACCUGUGUUACCAUCAGAAAAGGACUUUAAUGGAAGUGAUGCCUCUACCCAGCUAAAUACACAUUAUGCAUUUAGCAAACUAACUUACAAGUCUUCCAGUGGCCAUGAAGUUGAGAAUAGCACAACUGAUACUCAGGUCAUUUCACAUGAAAAAGAAAACAAACUGGAGAGUUUGGUUUUAACUCAUUUGAGUAGGUGUGAUUCUGAUUUAUGUGAAAUGAAUGCAGGGAUGCCAAAAGGAAACCUAAAUGAACAAGAUCCAAAACAUUGUCCUGAAAGUGAAAAGUGUUUGCUUUCCAUAGAAGAUGAGGAAUCUCAACAAAGCAUUUUAUCAAGUCUGGAAAACCAUUCACAGCAGUCAACUCAACCAGAAAUGCAUAAAUAUGGUCAGUUAGUUAAAGUAGAAUUAGAAGAAAAUGCCGAAGAUGAUAAAACUGAAAACCAAAUCCCUCAAAGAAUGACUAGAAACAAAGCAAAUACAAUGGCAAAUCAAAGCAAACAGAUUCUUGCUAGCUGUACACUAUUAUCAGAAAAAGACAGUGAAUCCUCAUCUCCUAGAGGAAGAAUAAGAUUAACUGAAGAUGACGAUCCUCAAAUUCACCAUCCACGGAAAAGGAAAGUGUCACGUGUACCUCAGCCUGUGCAAGUGAGUCCCUCUUUACUACAAGCAAAAGAGAAAACUCAGCAAUCUCUGGCAGCCAUUGUAGAUUCUCUAAAACUAGAUGAGAUUCAGCCAUACAGUUCAGAGAGAGCAAAUCCAUAUUUUGAAUACUUGCACAUAAGGAAAAAAAUAGAAGAAAAACGCAAAUUACUGUGUAGUGUGAUUCCUCAAGCACCUCAGUACUAUGACGAAUAUGUAACAUUUAACGGAUCAUAUCUCCUGGAUGGAAACCCCUUAAGCAAGAUUUGUAUUCCCACAAUUACACCACCACCUUCACUGUCAGAUCCACUUAAAGAGCUUUUUCGACAACAGGAAGUUGUAAGGAUGAAACUACGUUUGCAACACAGUAUUGAAAGGGAAAAACUCAUUGUAUCCAACGAACAAGAAGUUUUGCGAGUUCAUUACAGAGCUGCAAGAACAUUGGCAAAUCAAACACUGCCAUUUAGUGCUUGUACUGUUUUGCUGGAUGCCGAAGUAUACAAUGUACCAUUGGACUCUCAGUCUGAUGACAGUAAAACUUCUGUGAGGGAUCGCUUUAAUGCAAGACAAUUCAUGUCUUGGUUACAAGAUGUGGAUGAUAAAUUUGACAAAUUAAAGACCUGUCUUUUAAUGAGGCAACAACAUGAAGCUGCGGCUUUAAAUGCUGUCCAGAGGUUAGAAUGGCAGCUCAAACUCCAGGAACUUGAUCCUGCCACCUAUAAAUCUAUCAGCAUUUACGAAAUCCAGGAGUUUUAUGUUCCCCUUGUUGAUGUUAACGACGACUUUGAAUUGACUCCUAUAUAGCAGUCAGUACUUCCUGAUGGUAUUGUCCUAAACUGGUGAUGCUCAAGCAUUAUACUGUGGAAUACUGCCUUUUGACAAAAAUACUCAUGCCUUUACAAUUGUUAGUAAAGUUCGAUUAUAGUUGGUUAUGUAGUAAACACUGUCAUUUUAUAAAAAAUGAGAAUUAUUUUGGAUCUUAGAUCCAAACACAGUUUCUAAUAGAAAACUAUUAUUUAUAUUGGGAAAGGUAACUAUUGCAUUAGAGCAUGUUGGCAGACUGGUAGGUAUUUAAAAAGUUGAGAAUCUGCUAACAGCGCUGGAAGUUGUUAGCGCUCUAAGUAAUAAGAUAACCACUAGUAUUCAAAUCUCUUUCAGGUUUUAUUAAAAAAUAUAUAUCAAUAAACUAAAAGGUUCAAUUCCUACCAAAUAGUUUCUAAUGUGGGAGAAAAACUUGGCACAAAAUUUCUUCAGUUUAUUAUCUGUAAAUUGUACAGUUUUCUUUUUGAAAGUUUUAAUAUUGUCUUCCUUUUUAAUAACUUAUUUUAUACAUAUUGUGCAGAUGUAAAUCUUGUAAUUAAUGGUCAAACUGUAUAAAGGGAUUGGUAGUCAAAACAUGUACAAAGAAAUACCUGUAAAACUGUUUUGUCUCAUGUUUUAUUGGACCAAAGUUGUGGUUUGUAUGGAGUGUAGUAGUAGUGUGUACAGGUAGAAAACUUUUAAAUACAGCAUGCAGGUGUUUCAGUUAGCUUGUUUUCAUCACCAUAACUGCAAAGAUGUGGCUUAGUUGUAUUGCAUGCUUCCUAUAAUUUAACUCUCCAUAAUUGAUGCCUGCAGUAGUGUAAGGCAUUUCAUACUAGUCUCCUCUAGUAGACCUGUGACUUACUGUGUUGGACAUAUUAUUUAGACUUAGUCAUACAAAGAAACUUAGCUCUUUUUUCAUCUCACAGUAAAGCCUAUUUCCCCAGGAAAAAAAUAAAUGCCUUUGAAUGAAAAUUCUGAAAUUGUAAAUGUCUAUUUUAAUAUUCACCUAUGAAAGAAUCUGUGAAUAUAUGUAAAUACGUUUAAUAAAUUUUAUUGGUCAUGUUAAAUCAUUGUAAAACUUUUUUACAUUGCUUAAUGUUUUAAGCUUAAUAGCCUUUGCACUUUUAAAAUAAAAACCAAGUAUGCAAAUCAAAGAUAUUUGGUAGUCAAAAUAAGUAAAAGAAAUAUAGGAAUAUUCCAGUCAAUCUCUGAAAUGUUUAUGAAAAACAGGUUAAUAUGUUGUAUUUUUUUCCUUGUAUCAAGAUGCAAAACAUAAUUUGCAAAAUUUUAUAAUUGAAAUAAAACUUGGUAUGCUGUUUUAUAAUAAAUUAGCAAUAUACUUUAAAAAAAAUCCAGUUUCUCCUAUAACAUGAUGUAAAUUAAAUAUUCAGGAAUAUUUCAGGUCUGAAAUCUGCUGCUGAACUUGUUAGACAUUUUUGAAAGGAAAAUUAGGUUAGCGUACAAUUUAUCAUAAAUAUAUGAGGUAAAAUUUGCAAAACUUUCCACAGUACUUUCUUGAAUUAUAAUACUGAAUGUUUUCUGUUCCGAUAGAGAAAAGUGAAGCAAAUAUGUGAGGAAUGAAGUGAUCUAGUGCAAGUUGGUAAUUCCAGCUAAUGGGAGAGAAUGUAAAUGUGCAAAGGUACAUAUUAAGCUUAGGGAUUUUUGAAUUUUUACGUCAGUUUAUAUUUUAAUUCUUACUGUACUUGGCAUGCGCAAUAAAGCAGCACAUGUAAAAAAAAAAUACACAGUGCAAGGACUUUAUUAUAAAGGUUGGAUGUAGUUUUCCUUAGAAAUUUAGGUGAGAGAUUUUGGCCUUUUUUAUUGGAUAAAUUGGGCCAGAAAGGCAGGGUAGAUUUCGAAGCACUGGUUCUGUUGAAGUUAAGUUUAUUAAGCCUGGGAACAUUAAAAGCUAAUUUAUAAAAGCAAUACUUUUUAAUAUGAAAACUUACUGCAAAGUUUGUUUAUACUUUUGCCUAAAAAGGAAAUUGGAUGGGAUACUGUGGCAAAUCAUAAAAAACCAGAUAAUUGAACUUUGAAGUUAUAGAAAAUCAGAGAGGGGUAAGUUUAUAGGGCAUUUUGUUCUGAUGGUUCAACCAGAGGUCUGGGAAAUAGCACUGUUGGCCCAAACAGAACAGGCUUUUAGAAGAUAAAAGCGACAAGAAGGAAUCUGGUGAAUUUUAGUCAUCCCAGCUUUUUAGUCUUAACCACAGUUCUCACUCUCUUAAAUGGUACCUCAAAAAGCUGGAGCCUCUCUGCCAUGAUUAUGCUUCUACAAAUUUCUUUUAUAAAGAGACUCAAAGCUAAUGAUAGCUUAAAAGAAAAGUUAAUGCCUUCUCAUUGGAAAUGUAUAAUCAAAUAAGUAGUUAAGGGCUUUUGGUAUUAAAGAUAUUCUGAAGCUCUGAAAUGCUAGAAAAAAAUUUGGAAUGGAGUAUAUGCCUGAAAAGGUUUUGGAUUCAGAAAGAAAAAGGAUGGUUAGUUUAAUCAGUGAUUCUUUUUAAACUCUUCAAAUAUCAUGAACAAGAUACUAAAUUGUACCUAAGGAUUUGUAUUUCUUUACAAUUUGUUCUAAAUAUCUGUUUAAUGACUAGUUGAUAUUUGUGCAUGUUAUUUAAUAAAGAGUUAUAUUUUUAUAGAAAAAAAGAGUGAAAUGUGUGCUAACUGUUUUUUUACUUAAUUUUACUUGGGCAGCUAGCAAAAUUGCAGAAAUAUGCAUCCUGGGAAAAGAAACAGCCUUUGAAGAAUUAGCCUUUCAAGUUCAAAUCUAUUUAAUAAUGAGAAGUCUCACAAGUGAAUUUUUAAGUACAGGCAUACCUCAGACGUACUUUAGGUUCCAGACCAUCUCAGUAAAGCAAAUACCACAACAAAGCGAGUCAGGAGGAAUUUUUUGGUUUCCCAGUGCAUAUAAAAGUUUUGUUUAUACUAUAUUAAGUGUGCAAUAGCAUUAUGUCUAAAAAUAUGUACAUAAGUUUAAAAAUAUUUUAUUGCUAAAAAUGGUAACAAAGUGAGCACAUGCUGUUGGAAAAAGAGCACCAAUAGACUUGCUUGAAGCAGGGUUGCCACAAACCUUCAAUUUGUAAAAAACGCCAAUAUGUACAAAGCACAAUAAAGCAAAGCACAAUAGAACAGGAUUGCCUGUAUUAGACAUGCUACAAACUUCAUAACUGGAAACAUCUCAAAGACCCCAUGAAGCUCAUUUGAAUGGGACUUAACAAUUAGACAGUUAUUUUAGAAAUUGAGUGCAGACCUAAAUACAUAGUUUUCCAAAAAGAAAAUUAUUGUCUCUGAUAUCUUAAAACAUAAAAACCCAAAAUUUUAUAUAGAAGAAAUUGACUCUGUAAAACGCAAUGAAAUAGUCCUCUUUUUAAACAGUUUAAAGGAAGCAUUUUCACCGUUUGUAAAAAUUAUUUUUAAAUAUUUAGGGCAAAAUUUUUGUUAGAUAAUAAUGGAAAAGCUUGUGUGAGUUUAGUGGUUAAAAUAUCUUGUAAUUCAUCAUUAUUUAAGUGACUUCUUGGGAGCCGUCUUUGUACCUAAAAUGGAGUUUUUUUUUAAGCCUCCACAGAGAUAGUCACCCAAAGUAUUUCCAGUCAGUAAAAGUAGAAUUCAUAGAAAAAACUGAGGCAAAUUAAAACAAUUCCAUUAAUCAAAAUGGCUUUAAACAAAUUAAGUAUUAGCAUAAAAAUAGCAAAAAGUACAACUAAAAAAAUGGUUGGGUUUUCCCAGUGGUUAAAUGCUAUAUAAUAACUGCAAAUAAAAGUUUUUUUGUACAUGGACAGCGUCCUCAUAAAAGAAAAUAGGCCAGGCCAGGCGCAGUGGCUCGCGCCUGUAAUCCCAGCACUUUGGGAGGCCAAGGCGGGCGGAUCACGAGGUCAGGAGAUCGAGACCAUCCUGGCUAACACGGUGAAACCCCGUCUCUACUAAACAAAAUGCAAAAAAUCAGCCGGGUGUGGCCGCGGGCGCCUGUAGUUCCAGCUACUCGGGAGGCUGAGGCAGGAGAAUGGCGUGAGCCUGGGAGGCGGAGCUUGCAGUGAGCCGAGAUCGUGCCACUGCACUCCAGCCUGGGCGACAGAGCGAGACUCCGUCUCAAAAAAAAAAAAAAAGAAAGAAAAGAAAAUAGGCCAAUAUGGUGAAACCCUUUCUCUACUAAAAAUACAAAAAUUAGCCAAGCGUGACGGUGCCUGCCUGUAGUCCUAGCUACUUGGGAGGUUGAGACAGGAGAAUCGCUUGAAGCCUGGAGGCGGAGGUUGCAGUGAGCUCACGCCACUGCACCCCAGCCUGGGCAACAAGAGUGAAACUCUGUCUCCAAAAAAAAAAAAAAAAAAAAAAAGUAUAUCACAUAUGUAGCAUGUGUUUACAAGUUUAAAAGGCACCACCUAUGCACUCAUCACUCAAGAGAAUAUCAAUAACUUUCUCAGUUUUUUUUCAUUGUUAUAGUCUGUAUUCAAUAAAAUUACCCAGAUCUUAACUAGGCAGUUUGAUAAAUCCUGACAAAUGUAAACACUCAUGUUACCAUCACCCAAAUUAAGAUAUUGUAAAACAUUUUCAUUACUCUAGAAAGUUCACUCAUGCCUCUCUCCAGUCACUACCCCUGAGGCAGCCACUGUGCUGAUUUCCCAUCACCAUACAUUAGUUGUACCUAGCCUUGAACUUCAUAGAAAUAGAGUCAUACAUACUUCCUUGUCUGCCUUGUUUCUCAACAUGAUGUUUUGAAAUUCAUCCAUGUUGCACCUAACAGUAAUGAGUCGUAAUUUAUUAAUGAGUAGUAGUGUAUUGUACAAAUUUGUUUAUUCGUUCUCUUGUUGGUAUUUGGAUUGUUUCCAGUUUGGGACUAUUGUUAAUAAACCUGUGAAUCUGCAAGCCUA